AGAUAGACCCGGAGAGACGGCGAAGGAGCUGGAAACCGAGCCAGGGCUGAGCCGGCUGACAACAGGUAAGGAGAUUCGGAGGACAAAGCGAGCUGUUAGGGAGUAUUUGGGAGUGGAUUUGGGGGCUGAAUGCAGAUCUUGGUAUUGGGAGGGUUUGCAUCACGUGGCAGGUGCGAGCCCAGAGAGACCGGCGCAGGGAUCCUGAUCUUGAAAGAUUGGGAGAGGGCAGGAGGCCAGUCUCUAUGGGGGCGGUUCCCGUAGGAUCACCAGGUGGGUUCGCGUGCCCAGAUUGACUGCUUGUGGGUGGCAUGGCCUCAGGUGGAGAGGCUUGCUGCGGACUCAGGCUGGCGAAUAGCCCUGGCGAACAACGGGCGGAGGGGAAGGUGUCUUUCAAGUCGGUAUUUACUCUGAACUGAGGGAAGAAAAGAACGGAGGCCGCGUCAGACCGAGAGCUGCUCUGCGGCGGCCAGAGAGGGAAUCCCAAGCUCUUAAUGGGCGGGGGUGGGGGUAGAAAUGUCUUUUUCUAUUGUGUUUGAGACCGGUAAUAUUGGGGAGGGGGAGAACAAGUAUUAUCCCACGCAGUACACCCCAAUCUCCCAGUUCAUUUCCUAAUCCUUAAACUCUGGUUUCAAACUCCCUCGCUUUGCUCUUCAGUUGCAGGUUCCGAUCUUUGGGUACUCCAGGAGCUGUUCUAUAGCCCCUGCUUCUGGACCUAUGGAUUCUCCAUCUAGCGUUUCUUCCUAUUCCUCCUACUCUCUCUCUUCGUCUUUUCCCACCUCCCCAGUGAACAGUGACUUUGGCUUCCCCUCUGAUAGUGAGAGGGAGGACAAGGGGGCCCAUGGGCCCAGGCCAGACACUGUUGGGCAGAGGGGAGGUUCACGGCCCAGCCCGGGUCCUAUCCGCUGCAGGCAUCGAUCGAAGGUUUCCGGUAACCAGCAUACACCAUCUCAUCCGAAACAGCGGGGUUCGGCUUCUCCUAUGGCAGGAUCUGGGGCGAAAAGAUCAAGAGAUGGUGAACUGGAGACCAGUCUAAACACCCAAGGUUGUACCACAGAGGGAGACCUGCUGUUUGCCCAGAAGUGUAAAGAACUCCAAGGAUUUAUACCUCCUCUCACAGACCUACUCAAUGGGCUGAAGAUGGGUCGUUUUGAGAGAGGAUUAAGCAGUUUUCAGCAGAGUGUGGCAAUGGACAGGAUCCAGCGUAUUGUAGGUGUUUUGCAGAAGCCACAGAUGGGGGAACGUUACCUAGGAACCUUGCUACAGGUAGAAGGGAUGUUAAAGACUUGGUUUCCACAAAUAGCUGCCCAGAAGUCAUCAUUGGGUGGUGGCAAGCAUCAGCUGACCAAGCAUUUUCCAAGCCACCACAGUGAUUCAGCUGCUUCCUCUCCUGCAUCUCCUAUGGAAAAGAUGGACCAGACACAGCUAGGACAUCUAGCUUUAAAACCAAAGCAGCCUUGGCACCUCACACAAUGGCCAGCUAUGAACCUCACCUGGAUCCACACCACUCCAAUUUGCAACCCCCCUCUCAGCUCCCCAGGUACUAUCUCCUUUAGCCAUGGUCCUUUAGGCACUGGAACCGGCAUUGGCGUCAUUCUUUUCCUCCAGCAUGGAGUGCAACCCUUCACCCACUCUGCCCCAACCACCCCAGUCCCACCUACUACAGCAUCUCCUGUCAUCCCUGGUGAGCCUAUGAAACUAUCUGGAGAGGGUCCUCGUUGCUACAGUUUGCCAGUAACUCUGCCAUCAGACUGGAGCUAUACCCUAUCCCCUCCCAGUCUACCCACCUUGGCCAGAAAGAUGACCAUAGGACACCGGGAGCAGCAGAGAAGCCAUCCUCCAGUUGCUGCUGAUGCUCAUCUUCUCAACCUCUAGCCCAGGGCAUACAGCUGUCCACUGUGACUUCUAAUUUGUGUAAAUAUUUAUGUAUAUAUGUAUUUUUACUAUUAAUGUGUGCAUUUGUGUUGAGGGAAGAUAAAUCCUUUCUGAUUAAAGAAAUUUUUUUAUACCUAAA